UAUUAGUUACAUUGUUUUGUUUUGCUUAUGGUGUCCUUUCUUGAUAAAGAAUUUGACAGUGCUUACAAAAAUACAUAAACUGCAAUGAAUAAGAUAAAUCCUUGAGAAAGUUAGUAGGGCAGAAAAAUAAGGCAAUGAUGAUAAUGAUUUGAUGACGAUGAAGUGGUUGUUCAGUGUGGCAUCAAUACUAAGCACUGCUGUAGACACUUUUGAUGUACUUACUCAUGUAAUCCUCACAAUAACCUUAGAAAUAUCUUAGGAUGAAAAAGAAAUUAAGGUACAUAUUCCAAGUCACAGAGUUAAAAAGGCACUCAUUUGAAAUCUGUCACCCGGCCUUUGAGCCUGGGCUCUGGGUCACUGAGCUCCCCUGCCUUCUCCGUAAAACCAGCAGGUAAAAUUACAUAUACAUUUUACAGGGUGCCACACAUUUGGUUCUAAGACUUAGCAGCUAAAUCAAAGCUGCAAAAGCAAUCAUAGUGUCAAUAGGAUAAAAUAUCAGUCAUUUUGAAGAUAAAGUGAAAUGCUUUACAGAUUUACUUGAAACUACCUCCACCAAAUAUUGAAUGCUGUGUCAAAUUGUCCCCAUAUCAAUAAUGGGAUAUAGUUCUUGAAAGCAUCCACACCUCCUAACAUCAACAUUUUAGCAGCAUUUUGGUGUAUCAAAAAGAGGUUUCCUUUUCAGUAUCUCCAGACACAAUGAUGUAGCUUGUGCAGUUGUUGGUGGAGUCACAUGUUCUGUGCCAGGAAAGCAGUGUUGUAUUUUGCCAGCUCAGCUACAGUCAAACCUGUCAGCCUUCAGACCUUUGGUAUUUUUGAAAUGCAGUCCAGGAAGUGCUCCAGAAAGUUUCACGGCAUGGUUGAGAGUGGCAGCAGAAAGUGGGACCAGGAGUCAUUGAGAUGGGUCAUUUUGAACAUGCAGUCAAGUGGCACAUCUUAAUAUGUUGGUAAACACAGAUGUAAAAGUAUAUCAAUAUGUCACCCCCACACUUUAUCCAAACACUUUGCCCAGUAUAGUUCAAAUGAGGUUUUCAAUUGCUUCCCCCAGAAGUGUGAGAUUCAGCAUCUACGUAUGGUAGGCCAAUUGCCCCAAGCCUAGGGCUGAUGCUACCUUGCUGUGCAAGGAAAGAGGUGAUUAGGUCUAAAUUUGACUCCUGGAGUGAGGCCUCAGGGUGGCUCUCCAAGGUGUCAAGGGGUACUGUAGCUGUUAUUUCACCAGUGAAAAGCGGCAUCUGCAUGAAACUCUCAGAGGUUUUUUGUUUUUGUUUCUUUUUUGUUUUGUAGCUAAACAAUGAACUAACUUGGCACUGUUUCAGAAGGGGCAUUAUAUCAAAGAACAUUCUUUCACUCUCUUUUGUGACUGACAAGAGACAAGCAAAGCCUCUUUUAUAGAGUGCAAUUAAUCACUAUCAAAACACACAGCUGUUGCUUUAAUUUGGCUACUAAUUUACUUAUAGUUUGAUUUUGCCACUUAAAAUGAAGUAUUAUCACUGAGGCAACAAUGUGAAAGUAUGCUGUUGUAAACGAUCUCUGAGUCAUAAAAUCUCCACUUGUUUUGCCAAAAACUUAAUCUGAUGUUCAAUGAAUCUCCCACUGCCCGAAGACCUCUGUAAUCCUGGGAUGCGACAUUUUGUUUGCAGACUCUUGAUUUAGUGGUGCCUCUGCCAAAUGAUCACUAACAAAUGAUAGCACAGCCAAGUGAGAUCAGUGAGAUUUGUGUCUGGUUUGUGUAAUGGUAAGCCGGUGGUGCAGCUGUCUGCCAGAGACUCCCCCUAAAAACUCAGAUAUAGUGAGCAAUAAUCAGCUCAUUAAAAAAUGAAACAGCCAAGAAGAACCGUUAUGGUGAUUGAAAACACUUGCUGGUGCAAGUGUGUCCAUGGCCCAGUCCACCAGCUGGCAGAGGUGUAGCUAGGGUUUCUGAGUGUGUGUAACUCCAGGGGGUGAUGUUUACAUAAACUACAAUAUGAACGGCGCCCCCUAGAGCUGUGUAAUAUGAUAUCCCUGCAUUUUGUAGUCUACACUUUUUACCUUUUCCAUGGUAUCCUAUUAUUAUUUAACACAUUUGUAUUUCCACUUGCCUAUAAACUCCUUUAUAACUUGUUUCAUUUUCUUGAUCUUCAUAUUCCCAGGCCCUAGAGUGCCUAUGGCAUAGAGAAGGGGUUUUCAUUUAAAGUUAUUCAAUGAAUGAAAUAAAAGUGCAAAUAUAUUUUUCAAAGCCAAGGAUUUUAGCUUUUGUGUUUUAACAAGUAAGAACUUUCCAAAAAUACCAUUCAUAUUGGUAUGUCAGCUCAGUUGUCACAUGAUAUAACAGUGAGGAAUCCUGCGGGUGCAAGUGAAAGAAGCCCAAAUCAAGCAGGUUUAAGUCAAAAAGAUAAAAAACACAUUUAUUGGUUCAUGUAACAGAAAAUCCCAGAAUUAGACCCAUCUGGCUCCAUCACAGUCAAAUCCAUUGCUCUAAAUGAUGACCUGACCACAUUCUUGCUCCAUCUCUCAGCUGUGCCUUUCUUUGUGUUGCUCCAUGCAACCUCGCUGUUUCCAUCCCACAUCAAGAUGGCCAUGAACAGCGUCAUACUAACAGCCAGUCUUUCAGCAAUCAUUUUCUCCCCAUCACAGCAAAAUCCCAGAUUUCAUUGUAAUUACACUGCCUUGGGUCAUGUGCUCAUCCUGAACCAAUAAUUGUGGUCAGAGGAUUGGAACGCUCCGAUGGGCAGGAGGGGAAGCGAGUGGGAAACCGAACCACGUGGCCUAAGAGGGUGGAAGAGGUUUCUUUUUCAAAACAAGAAGAAAUAGAUGAUAGAAAAAGGAAAAACAAGAUGUUUUCCUGACAUCAUUCCUCAUUUAACAGGUGUUGAAACUAGGGCUCAGAGAAGACAUGUGACUUGACAAUGUAAGUCUUCUGACACUGAGUCCAGUGUGUUUUUUACCUUAUCUUUCAUUAAUUGUUGGGCUGUUUCAGUUUGUAAGUGAUUAGAAGUAAGAUAUAUAUAUAUAUAAUAGAUAAUAGAUAAUCUGUUUUUUAUAUAUAUACGUCACGUAGCAUGGUGCUCUGAGAACACUGAAGAACAAGAAGGAGUGAAUGGGUUGAUUGAUCAUUAGAAUCAUAAGACUAUUUUUUGAGCCUUUGGUUCAGUAUGAUUCAGCUUGAUUUCCUAAUCUGUGAAAAAAGGCAGUUUGAUUUUUUUGACAGAUCAUACAAGUAGGUAGAAGCUUUUUCGGAAUUACUGGCAGUGAUUUCAACAAAAAACAAUCCAAUGCAAAUGGCUGUCUUAUUUCUCUGCACUCUUGACUACUGAAAUGUUUGUUUUGUUUGCUUUGAUUUGGAUGUGGUUCUAGUUUUGGUGAGAGUGAAGUGGCACUUUGGCCUGAAGGACUGUGUGUUUUAGAGAGUCACAGACAUUCGAUCUGCAGCCCACACUCACAGGAGACACUUUCAUAAAUGCUGCAUGAUUCCAUGUCCACAUCUGCACAGAGCAGCACAUCCUUGGUGAUCACAUUUUAUUUUAACUUAGUUUUGUUUGCUUUUUAAUUCACUUUUUGUGGCAGUUCAUCUUGAAGGUAUGAAAAGGAUAAUGAUUUCACAAGAACUUGAGUUGAACGCAUGCAGAAGAAGAGAGAGUUAAAGGGACUGCCCUGAAAUCAACCUGCUUAUUUAAGUAGAUUUGAAGAAAAACAGAGUAUGAAAACAACAAAUCAGCCUGACUUAUCUAAGAAGAGUGGAUAAAAUAGUCCCUGCAGGAGGAAAUGUGUAACCAAAUCCAGUACUUUAUCACAUCUUCAUGAAACCUUGAAAUAGCUCUAUGAAUUUAUAUUGUUUCCGAAAGACAUGUGAUCCGUGCUGUCUUAUCCUGCCCCACUGUGAACCCUGAAAUCAAUCCAUUGCUCUCUCAAACUUUGGGAAAAUGAUAUGCUGGAAAUGUCAAUGAACUAGCUGCAGUCACAGAACGUGUUUUUACUUUCUGAGUUUACUGAAGUGGAAGACAGAAAGGAUGCCUUCCUAAAAAAUAACCGCAUAUACUCACAGACCUAUAUUUUCUAGACAUGAGUACGUUUCUAUUAAAAUGCCUCCUUAACAUGAGAAAACCUUGUAAUUACUUUCUUUCACAAAUCAUUUGCCUCCUUUAUAUUUCCAAAGAUGGCCAAUUCUAAUUUCUUUUUUGGAGGUUUAAUAAAACAGAGGCCUUGGAGAAAGGAAAUGGAUACCGUUCAAAGAAAUCCACCUCCUGAAACACAAGAGGCCAGAGUUAGAUCUUUGGUGCUUCCAUCUUUCCACAAAUCACUCUCGUCUGUUUCAGCUUACAUUAGCUCAUAAUCAUUGUUUUGUAUUGUAGAUAUUCUGAAGAAGCACACUAUCAAUGGAUAAAAUGCAAUUUAAGAUUUCUGGCUCAUAAGGAACAGUGAAAGGUGGCUAAACAUUACAGUUGUAUUGCACUACUUAACUUGGAAUCCUUUCCCUGUAUGUUUUUUGCAAAUUUUCUGUUUGUUUAUUUAUUUCACAAUACUUUUAACAGUGCUAAUCUCUUACUCUGUGGAGCAGUUAACAAUUCUCCAACUGGUUAUACAUAUCCUGUGCCAUUCGUGUCUUACUGCUCCUCUUCAUAUUGUGGACAAUGAUUUGCUAAGUCUUUUUCCUUUAACUUACAGAUUACCAGUAAUUUUAAAUUCACAGAUAACUUUUAAAACAUUUUUAUAAAUAUAUUGGUUAAAUAAAUUAGAAAGUAAUGCAAAUGAAAGAAUAAUAAGAACAUGUCAUUGUAAUCUCUGAAGAGACCAGUAUAUAUAGCAUGUAUAAACGUAUUGUUGAAAAGGUAACAUCUGUAUAUUUCUCGUUUAGACCUAUAACUAAUAAAUAGAUGUUGGUAUCUCCUUGGGAAACUCCACAGAGUUUAUUAUUCAUCAGAUGGUUCUCUAAGUCUAUGUAUUGAGUAUUUGUCAAGCAAAAAGGGAAUGUUUGCUACUUACUAGCUUUAUAAACAUUGGGCAAGUUAAUGGACUUCUCUGUGCCUGUUUUUUAAUCUUCAGAAUGGCAGUAAUGAUAUUACCCACGGUGCUAUUGUGAGAAUUAAAUGAGGGAAAAUAUCCAAGUCCUUAGUAGGAUACCUGGCAUAUUGUAAGUGCUUCUUAAGUAUUUGUUAUUCUUUAAAAUAUUUUUUUCAAUAUUGUUACUAACCAUAAUACUGUUAGAGAAUUAUUUUCAAAACCAAGCUUUCACAUUUUGGGAGGCAGUGUCAUGUUUACAGCAGUCAGGCUUACCAAGCCAGAGGUACCUAGAUUCCUUUCCUAGCUCUUCUAUUAAACAGAUGGAUAGUCUUGGGACACACUCAAAGUUUCAAAACCCAAGUUUUCAUCUAGGAAAAACACAGGGAGCUUUAAAAAGUUGCGUCCCAGAGGGUAGCUGAAAAAUGAGAAGGUAAUAUUAUUAAAUAAUGUAGAAAAAUGGCUUCAUAAAGAAAACUUCUCUCACCUUUUUUUUUUUUAGAAACAGUAUAGGUAGCAAUUAUUAAACUGAGAAAACACUUCUCUAGUUUAACAAAUGAUGCUGAAGCUUGUCGUUAAAUCUCAUCCAAUUUUUUUUGCCCUAGAGCUGAACACCUUUGGCCAACAAAAGAAGUUACAUGCCUGAUUCUUAAAUUUGUAAACAAAUAAAACAUUAUUUUCUGUUUAUUUGUACAAUGUAGAAGUAGGUCUAAAGUAAUUGGCAACUUGGCAAGUUUUUAUUUUAUCUCAACAGUGAAAAUACUUAAGCCAUGGCAUAGCCCCAGACUUAAUUUCUUAUAUCAUUCAAUCUUCACUUUUGUCUUCUGAUAAAUGGAUACUAGCUACUUAAUUCUUAAAUCCAAUAUGAUUUCCAAAACAAACUUAUUGGGCAUGACUUCAACUAUACUGGUUGGUUAAUCUUUUACUUUUGAUGUAGAAUUUAAUUACAGACCUCAAAUAUAACUACCUCCAAAUACAACAUGAAAUCUUAAAACUUUAACUGCCUUUAAGCAUAGCCAGAGUCCUUGGAACUUUUUAUUUAUCUGCAGACUUCUACAGAAUAACAGUUUCAUGGCUGUGGAAACAUUUGUCAUAUUUCAAAAUCUAGUCUUUAUCUGUGGCCCUAAAGUAGAUUUAGGUCUUGCAAGAUUUUUUUAUCUUAUAAAAAUAGCUCACUUCUUUCAACUUCAUGUAAAGAUUGCAGGCUGGGCUAAAGUGACAAAGAAUGCCUUAAGGGGAACUUUGAAUGAAUAACUUUAAAGGAAACUAUUUUCACCAAAGACUUGUCCAGAUUUAAUUAGUUAUGAGGGUCAAAGGGAGGGAGAAAAGGCCAGAAGCCUGAAGGGAUUGCCAGAGUAAAAUGUUAAGGAGAAGUGAGGACUCACGUGGAGAAGGAAGUGUAGCCACUUGAAGUUUUAAUAAUUUUGUGACCUGGUGUCAAGUAUUGUGAUUUCUAAGGGCAGGAGAGGUAAAAAUGUGAAAUAUUAACCAGCACUGUUCAUUGCUAGAGGUGACUCAUACCCUUACCAUCUUCUUCAGUAUAUUGGGUAUAUUAUCCUUCAAAAUAAUAAAUUUUGGAAGAAUGUCAUUUGCUCCAUCAAAAAGGAUGAAAUAAAUGUGGUUUAUAAUGAACAUUUUCUCUCAACAGAGUUAACACUCUUCUUGCAAAGCCACAAAAAAAUGAAUUCUAUCACAUGCCACAAGGAAACUAUGAUUUUAAAAAAGGACACACAUGGAUCUAGAAUUGAUCUACUUUAAGCUAAAGAAUAUGAAUCAAUCCAUCAGCUCACUUAAACACACUUAGAAAAGGCAAAAGAUCAUUAUGAAUGUGGCUGGAACCAAUACCAAGGCCUCGAACUCAUGGUUCAAUGUUCCUUUCACCACUUGCUGAUGCCUCCCAAGCAGUACUUGAAAAUAAACAAAUUUUGAUGAUGACUUUUUUCAUGAACUCCCAGAAACUUUUCCUUCUGAUCCACCUGAGCCUCUGCCACAUUUCCUUAUUGAGCCUGAAGAAGCUUAUAUUGUGAAGAAUAAGCCCGUGAACCUGUACUGUAAAGCAAGCCCUGCCACCCAGAUCUAUUUCAAGUGUAAUAGUGAAUGGGUUCAUCAGAAGGACCACAUAGUAGAUGAAAGAGUAGAUGAAACUUCCGGUCUCAUUGUCCGGGAAGUGAGCAUUGAGAUUUCGCGCCAGCAAGUGGAAGAACUCUUUGGACCUGAAGAUUACUGGUGCCAGUGUGUGGCCUGGAGCUCCGCGGGUACCACAAAGAGCCGGAAGGCGUAUGUGCGCAUUGCAUAUCUACGGAAGACAUUUGAGCAGGAACCCCUAGGAAAGGAAGUGUCUUUGGAACAGGAAGUCUUACUCCAGUGUCGACCACCUGAAGGGAUCCCAGUGGCUGAGGUGGAAUGGUUGAAAAAUGAAGACAUAAUUGAUCCCGUUGAAGAUCGGAAUUUUUAUAUUACUAUUGAUCACAACCUCAUCAUAAAGCAGGCCCGACUCUCUGAUACUGCAAAUUACACCUGUGUUGCCAAAAACAUUGUUGCCAAGAGGAAAAGUACAACUGCCACUGUCAUAGUCUAUGUCAACGGUGGCUGGUCCACCUGGACGGAGUGGUCUGUGUGUAACAGCCGCUGUGGACGAGGGUAUCAGAAACGUACAAGGACUUGUACCAACCCGGCACCACUCAAUGGGGGUGCCUUCUGUGAAGGGCAGAGUGUGCAGAAAAUAGCCUGUACUACGUUAUGCCCAGUGGAUGGCAGGUGGACGCCAUGGAGCAAGUGGUCUACUUGUGGAACUGAGUGCACCCACUGGCGCAGGAGGGAGUGCACGGCGCCAGCCCCCAAGAAUGGAGGCAAGGACUGCGACGGCCUCGUCUUGCAAUCCAAGAACUGCACUGAUGGGCUUUGCAUGCAGAGUUUCAUUUAUCCCAUUUCAACUGAACAGAGAACCCAGAAUGAAUAUGGAUUUUCUUCUGCUCCUGAUUCAGAUGAUGUUGCUCUCUAUGUUGGGAUUGUGAUAGCAGUGAUCGUUUGCCUGGCGAUCUCUGUAGUUGUGGCCUUGUUUGUGUAUCGGAAGAAUCAUCGUGACUUUGAGUCAGAUAUUAUUGACUCUUCGGCACUCAAUGGGGGCUUUCAGCCUGUGAACAUCAAGGCAGCAAGACAAGAUCUGCUGGCUGUACCCCCAGACCUCACGUCAGCUGCAGCCAUGUACAGAGGACCUGUCUAUGCCCUGCAUGACGUCUCAGACAAAAUCCCAAUGACCAACUCUCCAAUUCUGGAUCCACUGCCCAACCUGAAAAUCAAAGUGUACAACACCUCAGGUGCUGUCACCCCCCAAGAUGACCUCUCUGAGUUUACGUCCAAGCUGUCCCCUCAGAUGACCCAGUCGUUGUUGGAGAAUGAAGCCCUCAGCCUGAAGAACCAGAGUCUAGCAAGGCAGACUGAUCCAUCCUGUACCGCAUUUGGCAGCUUCAACUCGCUGGGAGGUCACCUUAUUGUUCCCAAUUCAGGAGUCAGCUUGCUGAUUCCCGCUGGGGCCAUUCCCCAAGGGAGAGUCUACGAAAUGUAUGUGACUGUACACAGGAAAGAAACUAUGAGGCCACCCAUGGAUGACUCUCAGACACUUUUGACCCCUGUGGUGAGCUGUGGGCCCCCAGGAGCUCUGCUCACCCGCCCAGUCGUCCUCACUAUGCAUCACUGCGCAGACCCCAAUACCGAGGACUGGAAAAUACUGCUCAAGAACCAGGCAGCACAGGGACAGUGGGAGGAUGUGGUGGUGGUCGGGGAGGAAAACUUCACCACCCCCUGCUACAUUCAGCUGGAUGCAGAGGCCUGCCACAUCCUCACAGAGAACCUCAGCACCUACGCCCUGGUAGGACAUUCCACCACCAAAGCGGCUGCGAAGCGCCUCAAGCUGGCCAUCUUUGGGCCCCUGUGCUGCUCCUCGCUGGAGUACAGCAUCCGAGUCUACUGUCUGGAUGACACCCAGGAUGCCCUGAAGGAAAUUUUACAUCUUGAGAGACAGAUGGGAGGACAGCUCCUAGAAGAACCUAAGGCUCUUCAUUUUAAAGGCAGCACCCACAACCUGCGCCUGUCAAUUCACGAUAUCGCCCAUUCCCUCUGGAAGAGCAAAUUGCUGGCUAAAUAUCAGGAAAUUCCAUUUUACCAUGUUUGGAGUGGAUCUCAAAGAAACCUGCACUGCACCUUCACUCUGGAAAGAUUUAGCCUGAACACAGUGGAGCUGGUUUGCAAACUCUGUGUGCGGCAGGUGGAAGGAGAAGGGCAGAUCUUCCAGCUCAACUGCACCGUGUCAGAGGAACCUACUGGCAUCGAUUUGCCGCUGCUGGAUCCUGCGAACACCAUCACCACGGUCACGGGGCCCAGUGCUUUCAGCAUCCCUCUCCCUAUCCGGCAGAAGCUCUGUAGCAGCCUGGAUGCCCCCCAGACGAGAGGCCAUGACUGGAGGAUGCUGGCCCAUAAGCUGAACCUGGACAGGUACUUGAAUUACUUUGCCACCAAAUCCAGCCCAACUGGCGUAAUCCUGGAUCUUUGGGAAGCACAGAACUUCCCAGAUGGAAACCUGAGCAUGCUGGCAGCUGUCUUGGAAGAAAUGGGAAGACAUGAAACGGUGGUGUCCUUAGCAGCAGAAGGGCAGUAUUAACCACCAUGCUGGAAGGGGAAAUGAAGGACAAAAAUGCACAGGGAGUCUGUGGCCGUCCAGGUGAAUCACAGCUGAGGAGGAAAUCCAGAUGAGACCAAUGCACUUCACAGGCAAGACUGCAGCAGGAGCCAGAAGGAAAACAGAUACAACUGCCCAUGUACAUGCCCACUUUACUCGGACAUCAUCACGGGAGUUAAGAAAAAUUGUGUAAAUUUGUACCUUGAAUUUAGCUAUCAACCUAAUUUUCCUCUUAGUUGGGCUGUAUGCUGUGUGGUACAGGAUCUUACAGUUUCCUAGGAAACGCUUUUUAUUGCUAUCCAGAUAUAUGGAUAAACUUUCUUAACAAACCCAAUUUCUACAAAUGUUGUUUACAUCAAAUUGGACAGGGAUGCAGACACUGUCCAUGGCUCGUUCUAUUUUUGUUCAAAUCAUUUGAAGUUGAAGCUGUGGACGGUUUGUUGUGUCUAUUUCAGAUUAGUAAUUUACAGAGAAAUCACAGACUUUUGCUACAAAUCGUGUGCAUCAAGUGUCUCAGAUAAUCCUCCCAUCAGUGUUCUGUUUCUAGAACUUGUAGAACCAGUGUUACUGUUUGUAUCAGGGAAGUGGAGAAUCUAAGUGUAAAAAAGAAAUAACUAAGACUCCUAUUCCUUGGAGGGACCCUUCUGGUGCCCUUUGGGAAUAAAGCUGUAGCACUGCAGGGAAGACAGUGAUUCAUGUUCAACCCCACAAACAAGCAUUUUUUUCACAACAUGUGUGUUUGUUUGUAAUAUGCAAUAUGAAGUGUUUUUUUUUAAAGGUAUUAUUAUUAUUUACAGGUAUUCUGGUAAAAUGAUUUUUUUAAAUUUCUAUUUUUGUUAGCAGUGCUGUUUGUUAGUAUUUGGUUAUUGACUAGACCUGUCCCACCUUUUCACCUAUCAAGGUGGGUGUGGUCAUCAGUUUAAUUCAACAUGCAUCACUUCCUUGACCUUUUACCUUUCCCUUAUUCCACCCCAGAAAGGUGAUUGAUAAAUGCUGAAUGGCUUUGUCAGUCUGUUCCUUCAGCUUGCUCAGGCAGGGUCUUUCUUUCUCCUCUGAGGAGUCUUAAGGAGACGUGUUCUCUAUUAAGUUCACUUAAUAUUGCCGUUGUGUGGCCCCACGUCGACUCCCUAUGGUGCUCUACUCUAGAGGCAGUGUGGUUGGAGGAAUGGACUCUAAACUGGAGAUCAAGAAACCAGUUCUCAUUGUGGGUCUGUCACUGUCUUGUUGCGCCACCUUGAGAAAGUCAUUUAACCACACGACCUCAGUGUCCUCACUAGAAAGUGAAAGGGUGGGAUUAGAUCAUCUCCAAGUUCUGAAAUGCUCAACUUCCACCGUGAUGCCUCCAGUCUCAUUCAUCAGUCUGAAGACCACAAUGGACUCUGACCUGGAUCAUCAUUUAAAAAUCAUCAGCUGGUCUUUUGCCCAGGCUAUGUUACGCCUUUCAAGUAGUUCUGACAAGGAAGAUGAUUAUUCUAACCAGCAUUAUGAUGUUGUUUGUUUGGCCUGAGUCGCUCUGCAUCAUUGCAUUAUGCUGUUCACUGAGAGAUGACAUCCCUUUAUUAUCAUUUUCUUAGCCUCUCUUGGGAUGCCCCUGCCCCCAGCCUUCCUGACUGGUUGCAAAUUCUGUUUUUUAUUAUUGUCUUGGCAUCUUGAUAUCUAGACCACUCCUACAAGUUUAUCUGGCAGUAGGAACUUGGUGCAUUUUUUUCUACGCUACACCCCCCCACCCUUAAUCUUUCUUUGCUGUCAUAAUAUUCAGUAGCAUUUAUAAAAGCUGUCUAGUUAGCUCUUUAAAAACUUUUGUCCUGCAAAAUGUUUGUUAGUCAACACACUACUUUGUGUAAACAACUAUUAUGUUUCCUUGGGACCAUCACAAGCUCUUUAACAAACACAAGGACUCAAUUCAUUCAGCAGGUGGGGAUUAAAGAAUCAAAGCCCAGUAGCAAAACCAAAACUGAAGAACAAGCAGACAUGUGUAUGAAUCGGAACCUUUAGAACAUGACUGUGGUUUACUUUUAGGCUGGAGGCACACAAGUUGCUGAACAGACUUGAAUUAUACAUGUGCUUCCAUCUUUCCAUGUUUCCGCUCCUAUUUUGGUAGCAUCUUGAGAUUCCUUGAUGCCUCCGCCAUCCUCAUCCCUGAGGAACUGCUGAUACCUUGCUAUGGAACCUCUUCUUUCUUUCAUGCUUUUUAUUCCGUAUCUUCUGUUUUGGACAUACAUACAUAUAUUCUAUAAAAUCUCUCUCAGCCCACCCCCUGCAUUAGGAUUUCCAUAUUUAAAAUAUUUGUACACUGACUGGGGAAGGGAGAGAUUGCACUAUAAACAAGUUCAGUGGAUGUUUGUAGCAAUGAGUAAAACUGUAUUCUAAAUUAAAAAUCAAAUAUAUAUACACGCAGUUAUACACACACAUUUUUUAAAAGGAGGAGGAGGAAAGAGAGCUAUUGUCCAUUCCUACAUUUUGAAAUAAACUUGUCAAGAUUACGCAUCAGUACCAGGGUUGUGGAAUCAUCUAUGGAAAUCAAGAACUAGAAUCUGAACUGAAUGGUCAAAGAAACUUCUAUGCCUAGUGAAAACUAGAGGGGAGCAACUAUGUAGCUAUGAACAUGAAUCAAUUCCAUAACUGUUACUAAAAACUUAUUUUGACUAAAAAGUCACCAACACAGAACUAUUGAACACAAACAGGAAUUGUUUGUCUUACUGAAGUCACUGAGAACCCUUGGGGUUCACUUCAGAUGCUUUUUUGGUUCAACUUCCCACCACCAGAAAAGGGAAAAGUGAUUGAUUUCGUGUGUGAGGUACUCAUCUGUCAGAACCCUUAAUGUUUCCUAUUAAGUGAAUGACAACUUCCAUACAUACACUAUUUAUACCAAAUAAUUUUCACUACAAAUUCUGAUUUCCUUCUCCUUUGGAGUAAAGUAAUAGCUGUUAGAUUGCUUUCAAACUUAGAAGGUCCAGAUAUAACAGUUCAUUUCAUAGGAAGCCACUUCAUCAACCAUUCUAUGUGAUACAUCCUGCUUCUUUCUACACCGCUGGAGAGGCAGUUUGGCUGGUUUCAUUUGGAUAGAAAAAACUAUCAUUUGUGCAUGCUGCCAUCUAGUGGUGUACAACACAAUCUAACCUGAGUUUAAUAUUCACUAGAAUGUGUUUGACGAAGGGAAUGAAAACCUGUAGAGUUCAAGGACCUUUAUGACAAACAGAUGUAGGGAAAUUUUCACUUCAAAUUUAUAAUUUUCUUAUUCUCACUUUUUUUUCAUUUGCAUCACUCAUCUCAAUAUUAGGUCACUGUGAGCCCAGUACAUCAACUCAUUCAUACACAACAUAUCUUCAGUUGCUUCUUGUAACAGAACUAUGUAAAAUCUAUAUAAAACAGUCUUUGAAGAGUUGUCAUUUUUAACACUUAUGGUUUUCAUUGGGGUUUGUAUACUUUAAAUCUCCUUUUAGUUCCUUAAUAUUUAUCUUUGGAAAUGUAAGAAGUAUCUGCUUAGAAAGAAAUAAGUCUUAUAUAUGCGAAUGGAAUACUAUGUCUAGGGAAGAGAAAAUUGGGGUUGUUAAUCAAAGGGAAGAAAGCAGCUUCUUUUCUGCUGAAUUUGGGAAUCCAAAGGCAGAGGUUUCAUCCUGUUUUUAUUUUCUUCUUAUCACACUCUUUCAAGUUUCCUUAAUGUAUCUGGAAGGAAUAGAAGUUGGAUUCAGAAUUGAUAACUGGCAUGGUGAUGACAAACCUGUGUAACACCAAGGUUCUCACAGCUAACAGCUGUUUCACAAACGGCAUCUUCCAAAUGAACAGUCACCUCUGCUAUGCAGAAAACCCCCAUCCUGCUGUGAGCAAGUUAGGCUCUUCAAGAACUGGACAACUUUUGGGUGAGGUGUUCAAUAUCAAACUGCAUAAUCAUUAGCCAUUUUCAUAUAUACUAUUUUAUAGAUUUAAGUCUCUCAACUAUCAAAAAGUAGAGCGAUUUUCAGGAGAAAAAAGUCGUGGGGACUGAGUUCAGGACACCCUGAAACUAUGCGACCAGUAAUUUUUUUAAGGUAUUUUUUCCUACAAGUAAGGUAUCUGAAAAGUCAACGUUUUGAGGGUGGAAUCAAGACUUUUCACUUCUCCUGGCAAAGAGCAACAAGGCUCUUGUCUCGUGUCCUUCUGUGUGUCUCUGUCAGGAUCACAGCAGCUGUGCUCUUGGUCUGCUUACUCCUCUGUAAUCCACGUAUGCAGAAGGGAGUUAAUAAGGUGAUCACCAUCUCCCCAGAAUUCAAAGGUCUUUGCCUCUAUAAGGUCUGCCCCUAUGGGGCCAGGAAAAUAUAAACCUAUAUAAGGACUUGCAAGAGAGCAUAAAGAAGGUAGAAAAGGUUUACUUGUUGGGUUUUCAAGCCUUCAAGUUGAAUGAGUCUUAGCUUUUGCUGGGCAGUUGUUCUGGACAAGUCAUCAGUUUCAUGUGGAGAACUCAGUGUAAGCCCAAGGCUAAUGAAUGAGAGGGGUCCCAUGGAAACACAGCUGAAAUGAAAUGGGACUUUAUCCAUCUUCUUUGAGAAUGGAAGAGCUUUUGUGAAGCAGUACAUCAUUGCUCAAGAUAAUGGUUGAUAAGCAUUAGAUUUUAUAGAUCUAAUAAGGAAAAUAUUUUAUUAUCUCAAGUUAACAAAACAUUUUUUUACCUCUCGAGUGCCUCAUAGGACCAACUAUUACUCUUUGGCUUUUAUUUUUCUUUUUGUAUUAUUUUUAUAUAUUCUUUAACCUUGCUGAGCUAGUAUUGACUGAAAUCUUUAGAACUUUGCCUCUGGGCAAUGAAGUAAUGUUUCUCUACCCUAAGAUAUCUAUUUGUAUAAUCUCUGGCUGUAAUGAUCACUUUGGAAGAUUUCCUUUGCAUCUCUAAUUAUUUCUUUUUAAUGGAAUAAGGCAUAAGGGGGAAUAAAUAUAUUGUAACCAAUGUUAUGUAAACCCAUAUCCAUACAGGCCAGGAAAGCCAAAUGAAGUCAUUUCCAGAAUUCUAGUGUGAAAAACCUAUUUUUGAAAAGUGGGGAGAUGGCUUUGUGUAGAACUGGGUGGGUUUUCUCUGCAGACUAAGUCUAGCCAUGAGCUUCCAGAUCCUUUAGUUUUAUCAGCCUUGUGCUUACCCCAUUUUCAUAAAUGCUACUUUAACAGCCAGUCUUCAUAAGUCAUGGUUCCUAGGUUUUCCUGUCACCUCAUUGUAUUCAUCUGUGGUAGGAUAUUAACGGGCUCAUUCAACCAAAUGUAAUGUGUGCCUCAGACCUAUUUAGCAUGGUUGGGGGGCAUCAGCAGGACAAACCAACAGGUACUCCGCAAGUGUACUGGCACAGCAAGCCCACCAAUUAUUAGCAGCUCUUCAUCAGCCUGCUGUCUACUCAGACGCUUGCCUACUGAAGGGACCUGUCCAGAGAUCUUCUGGAAUCCCAGGUUGGGAAUCUCUGCAGAAUGUCGUGACAGUUGUGGCCCAACUAGCUUCUGAGUAGAAACAAGGAAGCUACCCUGAGAUAUAGUCAGCUGCCCACCUGCCAUAGUAUUUGCUACUGAAUGCCAGCCUUUUAACAUACCAUUUCAGAUUUGUCCUUCAACAAAAAUAUAAAUUGCAAGUCAUACCAUUUAAGGGUCUUUUACAAAUAUGUCUAAAUUGUGUGUCAUUUUUAAGUUCCAAAGGUCUACUGGACUAAGUACUAUCAGACCAGCUGUAGAACCUGAUGGCGCUGAUCCGGGGUGGAAUAACCCUCAGUACUGGUGUGUAGAAGAUGAAUUGUAGGCAGGUUUUGCUGAUCAGCAGCCUAAGGAUUGAUGGGCUCUCUUUUGGCCUCUGAUCCUGAGCACUAUGGAGGCAGCAUCAGAGAAUGGGGACCUGAGCUACAUAGGUUCUCAAUGUUAAAACAACUCUGUUCGGAGUGACAUAUAAGAGCAAGAAAUCUACAGCUGGUGUAAAAUACCUUUGCCUUUUCUAUCCCGAAAGUAACAAAUGGCAUCUGUACAUGUAGGGGUAAAAACUCAGAUGUCUACUCCUCCAGGCCAUGGACAAGAAAAAGUACAGCAGUCAGAACAGUGGAACAAGUGAUUUGCAUUCUCUUCUUCACGCUUUCCUAGAUCUGCCAUUGGUAGCGCAGCCCUCGCCCUCCAGACAUAAUGCAUCGAGCCCAGUUGCAGGGAACAUCACUGUGUGUGUGUGAUGUCAUGGUGUUAUAUGUGUUGAGUUUAAUGUUGAGCUGAAGCAAGUUGGUGACCUUCCUCUUUGCUCUUUGUAAAGAAGACACCAAUGUUUGUCAGAGAAAAAUCCCCAGCAGUCGUGUUGAAGAGGCAGUGUCAUCCACCUACUGUCCCCUUUGGAACAGUUCAACUGCAGAAAGGUCGGAUUGAGGUUUUGUGCUUUGUCGUUUUUCUUUUUUAAACAAAACAUGACAACCUUGGCUUUUCCGAUAUGGAACACUUUUGUUGUUGUGGAGUUCCCUCUUGCUGUAUCUUCUAUGCAAUUCCUUUUCUAAAAAAACCCCCCGGCAGAGGCAGAGUGCCCUCCGGAUAUCUGUCCGGCGCCUUGCUGAGUGGUGGAGGUGAGGGAUACCAGCUCCGGGUGUGCCUCUUUUCUCUCCCUGGCUGCCAAUCCUGAUUUUCCCUGCAGUCCCCUUGGUUUGUAAAUUGCCUGCAUUUAUUCUGUCAGCCAACAUGUACAAAAUGUAAGAAAGAAUUUUUAAACAGGUAAUAAAUUAUAUUUAUAAGCAACAAA